GUAGGGGUUGUUGGGCUUCAGGGCAGGAUGCAGUGUGGUGGGGGCUGAAGUCUCAGAAUGGCGCUGUGCUACAGUUGCUUAGGACUUGGGACGUGGGCUCACUUUCUAGAGCAAUGAUGUUGCAUGAUCUCUAGGCAGGUCCUUAAGCUGUUCUCAGGGCCUGUGAUGGGUUUUUCUGUGGCUAGGGCUGGCGGAGUCCAUGGUGGGAAUAUUGACCACUGUGGAUCUCUCACUUACCCUUUCCCCUCACUGAAGAGCCUCUUCGGGCUCUCAGCCAGUCUUGGCCAAACUGGCUGUCUUGCGUUCCUCUCUUUUCAUGCCUCGGGUGUUUCCUCUUACUUCUUAGAUUCCAGUGUUCCUUCUUAGAUGCUCAGUUUGAAGAUUAUAUACUUAAUAUUUUGGUUCUUCUUUGUGGAGAAGAGGAAUAUUGGAAGCCUCCAGUCAGCCAUCUUGAAGUGAUUUACCUAUUGUAUCUUUAAAAAAUCUCAUGGACUAUUACUAUUAUUACUUACAUAGUCAAUGUUUGUUGAGAUUUACCCACAUAUUUAGCAUGUUCUUUGCUUUUUAUUCUUGACAUCUCAGACCUUUCAUCUGGGAUUACUUUUCUUCUUUCUGAGGUAGAUCCUUCAGAAUUUCCUUUACUGAAGGUCUGCUAGUGGCAUUCUGUCUUGGUUUAUGUUCAUUUGAAUAUGUCAUUAUUUCAGCUUUGUCCUCGAAAGACACUUUCUGUGAUGGUAAAAUACCAGGUUGGCAGCCAUUCUCUUUCAGUACAAUGAAGACAUUCUUUUGACUUUUGGUUUCCAUUAUUGCUGUUGAGAAUACAGCUGUCAGUAUUUCUCCUCUGACUGUAAUCUGUCAUUUUAAAAUCUAGCUACUUUAAUCUUUUCAUGUCAUCUUUGGUGUUUUACAGUGUCACCAUGGUAGUUCUGUUUGUAGGUUUUGUUGAAUCUUGAUGUCUUGGCAAAACCACACAUAUACAAAUACACUGUUUACUUUCAUUGUGAGAAAUUAAGGAUUUCAGAUGGCACAAGUAAUUCAAGGUUAUAAAGCAGUUUUCUUGAUAGCCUUUUGAAUAUUGAGUACAAAUAGUCCAAACCAUGUUAAAGUAGAAUUUGGAAGCAGUUAAGAGUAGAAACAAAUGUAUGCCCACUGCUGCCACAAUCUGUUUUAUAAAUAUUCCCAGAAGUCCCCAGAAGAACUUUGGGAUUCUGGGGAAAGUAUGGUUAAAAACUUGUAGUUGGCGUUCACCCAAAGAUAAUGCAUGUGUGAUUCAUUUUGCUUUUUUUCAGGCAUCGCUUAUUAAUUAUGGAUAGGUUAAUAGUGGUUAGUACAGUGAAAUACUCUUUUUGAGUAGAGAAAACAUUUAGGCAAUACACCAUUUAUUUAGAUGUCAGCUAUAAAAUAAAAGUACAGUUUUUUAGAUAUAAUUUGUAUAUUCUUGAAAGCAAAAUAUUUUUCUAAUUAUUUUUCAUUCUAAUUUUUAACAUAACAAUUUUCUUCUAAUAGAAAAAGUAAAUGCUCAAAGCAAAAUAUUGGGAAAAGCUUUUGGAUACAACUAUCGCAAGCAGUGUGGUAUUUGGCUUCAUACUACUUUUCUUUUCUCUUACACAUAUAACUUUAGAAAACACACACAUGGUCAAAUCAGUGGAGAAAUGUUGAAAUAAGUUAUGGUAUAGUUGUUCUUUAGAAUAAUUAUAGAAUAAUUUAGAAUGAGAGUGUUUCUAGUUAUACUAAGAAGGAAAGCUCUCUAAGAUAUAUUAAGUGAAAAAAGUAAGUCCCCUCAAAUAUAUACAGUGUAAUACUGUUAUGUCAAAACAAAAUAAAUAUGUAUUUCUAUAUGUACCUUUAGAAAUAUGUGUGUAAAUAUGUAAAAAAAAUCUGGAAGGCUAUAUAUCAGAUCUAUAAUACUGAUUAUUUCUGCGAAGGAUGUUGAAUGGUAAGGGAAGUGGUAAUGGGGACUUUUGCUUUUAUCUGUGGCUUUUUUUUAAAAAAAACAAGAAUAUAUUUGUAUAUAGGAUUUGUGCUUUAAAGUAAAUAAAAUGACAAUUUUCGUUUGAAAAGGGGUUAUUGUGUAUAUUCUGCUUUCUUGCCUAUUUUUUUUCAUAAUCUGUUGUGACUGUAUUCCCAUGUAAAAUAUCUCUAUAAAUUGAAAUUUAUGUCUGCACUGCAUUCCAUUGUAUGGCUGUUCCAUAAUUUACUUAACCCAAUCUCUAUUUUGUUAAGCAUUUAGAAUAUUUCCAGAUUUGUUAUUAAACUAGAUGAUAUGAUGAAUACUUUUAUGUAUAUGUCUUUGUAUACCUCUCUGUUUCCAUAGAUAACUUUGCUAGGUUAAGGGGUAUGUUUUUAAGGCUGACAAGUGGUCUUUCAGAAAGGUAUACCCAUUUCCGCCAACCUCAGAAGUAGGUGAAAGUGUUUUUUUCCUACUCUGGCCAACCUUGGGAAUUAUUUUUCUUGUUAUUUUUUGCUAAUUAAAAAAACAAUUGUUUUCCAAAAUUUCAUUUCUUAGAUUACUAGUGAGAUUGAAUCUUUUUCUUUCCAUGUUUUUUGGUCAUUAAUAUUCCUUUAUAGUUUGCCUGCUAAUCACCUUUUCCCAUUUUUCUCUUAGCGUGUUUUUUCUUAUUGAUUUGAGUGCUUCAUUUAUUGCACAUAUCAACGCUGUGUCAUAAAAGUAAAAACUUUUUUCCAGUAGUUUGCUUUUUAAUGUUAAAGUUUUUUUAACUGAGAGAAAUAUUAUUUAUUGACUUGAAUGUUAAAUACUUUAAAUGUCUUAGAGUUAAAUAAUUUCAAAAGGCACACAUAAUAUUAAAUUAAUUGAAUUCCAUAAAUUAAAAAAAUCUGUAUUUUUGUUUAUUUUGAAUGUUUCUAUUCUUUUUUUUUAAACACAUCAUUCAAAUGACAAUACUUUGAAUAUUUCUUAAAAACACUGGAAAUGUUUGCUCUCAACUUUUAUAUAACAGCUUUUCCAAAAUAUUUUAAGGUCGUAGCACUUAAAACUUUAUAAUUAAUAACUAAAGAAAUACAGUUGCCUAGUUUCUUAAAAAAUGUAACGAGGCAUCUAUGAAUGCUCCUUGAUAGGACUUUACAUUAAAUAAAUGUUUAUUUAAGCUUUACUGGUUUCCUUUUCAAGGAUAGUAAUAAAGUUUAAUUUACUUUAAAACUUUUUCUAACAAUUUUUAAAAACUGUGUAAAUACUUCUGUGAUCAGAAACAGCAAAAAUUUGCAUUAGGCUUAUUAAUGGUAGAAAAAAAUCACUGAGAAACUUACUUGGAUAGAAAAUUCAGCAAGCUGUGUGGCUUUUUCCCUCUUGUUUAUUUAAGUUUUCUUUUCUUAGCUCUUGUUAUGACCCUACAAUCUUUCAAAGCCCUUAGCUUCUGGUUGGUGCUGUCACAGCUCAUCAGAUUUACUCACGAGACCCGUACAGAGUGUCUGGUGAAAAAGAGGAAAGGAACAUAUGUGCUGCUGUGUCCUUGGCAACUUGCAGAAGGCUGAAUCACGCAAAUGAAAACGAGGCCCAUUGUAGAUUUUCUUCUUGCAAACUUAUUUGAUCUUGCCGUUUUCCGUUUUCAACGUGCUCCCCCCUCUUCUGUAUCUUAUAUUUUAGUUCUCUCUAAAAAAUAAUAGAAAUUUAGGAAUGCCCUGUAAGCUACCGUUUUUUCCCUCAUAUUGCCAUUCCCAUGUCUCCAGUGCAUAUAUACUUAUAGGAGUAUAUGGCCAGUCAUUUCAUUAAAGUCCAAAUAUUUAAUACAUGAAAGAGCAAGACAGGAUAAUCCAGCAACUUAGAAUCAGAACUAGGACUACCUUGUUUUGAAGGCUAUGUGAAAAAUUUUUUUAAAAUCUCUUAUUUUUCUUGUCUUUUUUGGGGAAAGUUUGUAAACUCAUUACUAUUUUGUCUCUAUAAUUUUAUUUAUUAACAUAAUAAAUAAAUACAAAUUAUUAGUCUUUGGAGAAAUUAGUCUUUUGAAAAACUAAGAAGUAAAAGAUUCUUUUAAAAGUUUGCCCCCAGUAUUAAUUGCUUUCAUUAUUAUGGGAUGUUCAAAGUUUUUAACUUUAGCUUCAGAUUUAUGUAUCAUUGAUUGUAACUUAAUGACCUACACUGGUCUGAAGUGUCAUCUUGUAGCCUAAUUCUUUAAGCAAUUGUGACCUUACAGACUAGGAAGGAGGGCAAGCAGCAAACUUCCAGAUGCCGAGUAUAAGGUUGCAGGAUCCCAAGGGUAUAGAGGAAUUCUUCUGGUCCAAAGGGAACCGUGGAGGAGGGGAAAACCUAGAAUCAGGAAAGUGUAGCAAAGCAUUCCUGUCCUUUGGCAUCGUAGGCUGCCAGUGACCAUCUUAACUCUUUUUGAUAAAACCUUCCCGUUUAUUGGGUCUUCUGUCCCCCUACAUCUCACAGAUACAGCUUUAUUUAGAAUUGGAACUCAGUGGUAACAUGGCAUUUCCUUCACAACUUACUUAAAUAGACCUUAAAGGUAAUUAAUUAUUUUGGGCAGUGUUAGCUGCUUCUUUGAAUGCUGGUUUAUUUUAUGGGCAAGUAUGUGUGUGGUUUAGUUUUUUCUUAAUUAAAACUUUAAGGGAGUGGGUUUUAAAAAUCUAAACGUUUGAUGUUUUAAAAAAAUGUAACUGGUCACUUUAGUAGUUUUUUUUUUCUAUUUUGAAAAACUCUAAUGUUUUCCUUCUUAACUGUUUCAAAGUUUGUCUUUUGGGAAUUUUUUUGUUCAGCAAACAAGAAAUAGGUCUACUUUCCACACUCCCAUCCCAUUCUCAUUUUUAAGAAAACAAAACUAGAAAUUGUGGCUGCUUUUUGCUCUUUGUUCAGGUAUGCGCAGAGAGGAGUAUGUGGUAUCUGUAACUUGUGCUUCAUCUCUCUAAAUUUUAAAAUUAAGAUUUUAUAGCUUUUAAUGCAUGUAUUCACCAACUUUCUCCCUGUUUUUGUAGGACUGUGUAUGUUCAGUUACAGCCACAUAAAGCAGCACUUUUUAUUUUUCUGUGUAACAGUAGGUCAAAAGUGGCAGAGGUGCAUAUAACUAAGGUUGUAAAAAGUUCGAGGUGUGUUAGUCCCACUAGAAGGCUUCUGAAUAAACACUUGAGUAUUUACGUAGAUUUUUGCCCUUAAUGUAGUUUAUAAUAAAAUAUGGACUAAUAUACUGAGUAUAUUCAGUACUCUUGUUUGGUAUAAAUGAAAUGGUUAGAAAUGCUGUCAACCUAAAUGACUGACUCAAAAGCUAUGAAAUUUAAUACAGCUGAUAUUUUCUUUUUCAUAUGAACAGCUUGGAACAAAUGUUUUGCUUGUGCAAAUGAGAUGGCUAUUAUGAUGCAAAGAAGCAUCUUGGAAAAAAAAUUUCCUUUUUCUGUUUUAAGUGUUCCAGCUAAAUACUGCAACAAUUGCAAGCAGAGUCUGGAGAUUUUUCUUUCUUGCUUCUGUUGUAUGAUAUAUUUUAGCAAGUUCUCUUGAGACUAUUAAAAUGUCUUGGUUUUUAGGACAUGUGAUCAGGUGGGGAUAACUUUGUCUAUAGAUGCAGUGGGUUAGCAGUUAGAUUUUGCAUGUCUUCUCAUUUCUUUCUAGUUUCUCUGACCCCGGGUAACCUUUGGAAGGACCUUUGGUUCUUCUGAAGGCAGGAGUGAAGGAGGUUUGAGCAGGUGACUGAUGAUCACUGUCUCUACAGUCCACAGACAAUAUACGAAUUACUUUAGCAGUCCCCUUAGUCCCCUCCUCCCACUCCUCCCCCCUUAAACCAACAAAUGCAAAUAGCUUCAUCCCCAUUUGCUAGAAAUUCAGGCUUGCUCAGGCAACAUGGGCUUUGUUGACUUGCUUUCUCCAGAAAGGCAAUUUUAUUCCUGGUAAGGAGCAAGGCUAUCCUAUCAUUUGGAACCUAAAUCACCUUAACGGUAAAAACAGCAACAACUUGUUUCUCUGGAAUAUUGAUAAAGUUCCUAUUGUAAAGAAUAUAGCAAAAACAGAGUCUUCUCCUUCCGAAGCAAGCCAGCAUUCAAUGCAGUCUCCACAGAAAACUACUCUAAUAUUACCAACACAGCAGGUCAGGAGAUCAAGUCGAAUUAAACCACCUGGACCUACUGCAGUCCCCAAAAGGAGCAGUUCUGUUAAAAAUAUCACACCAAGGAAAAAAGGUCCAAACUCAGGAAAAAAGGAAAAACCUUUGCCCGUGAUAUGUUCUACAUCUGCAGCUUCUCUAAAAUCGCUGACCAGAGACCGUGGCAUGUUAUAUAAAGAUGUCGCUUCUGGGCCAUGUAAAAUAGUGAUGUCUACAGUCUGUGUCUAUGUAAACAAACAUGGAAACUUUGGCCCUCAUCUGGAUCCCAAGAGAAUCCAGCAGCUGCCUGACCACUUCGGCCCGGGCCCGGUGAAUGUGGUGCUUCGCCGGAUUGUGCAGGCCUGUGUGGAUUGUGCCCUUGAAACUAAAACUGUUUUUGGAUACCUGAAGCCAGAUAAUCGUGGAGGAGAAGUGAUAACUGCCUCCUUUGAUGGGGAAACUCAUUCCAUCCAGCUCCCUCCAGUGAACAGUGCAUCAUUUGCUCUUCGCUUUCUUGAGAACUUCUGCCACAGUCUGCAGUGUGAUAACCUUUUGAGUAGCCAGCCUUUUAGUUCUUCCAGGGGUCAUACUCACAGCUCUGCAGAGCAUGAUAAAAAUCAGUCAGCAAAAGAAGAUGUAACAGAAAGGCAAAGCACCAAACGAUCUCCUCAGCAAACUGUACCAUAUGUUGUUCCUCUCUCUCCUAAGCUCCCCAAAACAAAGGAGUAUGCGUCUGAAGGAGAACCAUUGUUUGCUGGGGGAAGUGCCAUUCCCAAAGAGGAGAAUCUUUCAGAAGAUUCUAAGAGCUCAUCACUAAAUUCAGGAAAUUAUUUGAAUCCUGCCUGUAGAAAUCCUAUGUAUAUUCAUACUUCAGUCUCCCAGGAUUUUUCUCGAAGUGUGCCAGGCACCACAAGUUCACCACUAGUUGGGGACAUAUCCCCCAAGAGCAGUCCCCAUGAAGUUAAAUUCCAAAUGCAGAGGAAAAGUGAAGCUCCAAGUUAUAUAGCUGUACCUGAUCCCAGUGUCCUGAAACAAGGCUUCUCUAAGGACCCUUCAACCUGGUCUGUGGAUGAAGUGAUACAGUUUAUGAAACAUACAGAUCCUCAGAUAUCAGGCCCCCUCGCCGACCUCUUCAGGCAACAUGAAAUUGAUGGGAAGGCUCUGUUCCUACUCAAGAGUGAUGUGAUGAUGAAGUAUAUGGGGCUGAAGCUGGGGCCAGCAUUAAAGCUGUGUUACUACAUUGAAAAGCUUAAAGAAGGAAAAUACAGUUAAAAAAAUGUGUAAGUUUAGAUUGGACAUAAUUCUCAGGUGUACUGUUAACAUUUUAAUUUAAAAGUAUUUCUCUUAGCAGUUUUUGUUUUGUAGACAGUUCCCAUAAAAAUAUUUUAUCAGAAUUGCAGAACUGUAGUAACAGUUCAGUCAACUUUGUUUUUUUCCUGGAGUCACCAACCAGCUUUGGGAGACACAGCCGCCACUCCCCCAGUCUACUUCUUUAAAAAGCAUUUAACAGGUUAGUAUUGGCAUAUUCAAAUUGGCAGUUCUUUAUGUCUUUUUAAAUUUUCAUUGUACAGUUUACAAAUAUACUUAAUGUAGUUAACAGAGAAAAACCUUUGAUUUUGGUUAACCUUUAUAUCUAGAACCAAAACAGCUAAAUCCCAAAGGGGAAAAUAUCAGGGAUUGACAACUUCUAUAAUUAAAUCCAUGAGAAUUUUUCCUCACUAGAGAAUUUAAAGGUGCACCUGUAGAUAUCAUCUUUUCUCAGAUAUUUUGUGUGAUACUCUGUGGUGUUCUGUUCAUGUUCUAUCAGUAUAUCUAGAAAGGGAAUAGCCAUAUAAAUUAUUUUCCUUUUAUUAUUUCUCUGUAUGUUGUAUUUGAUCAUAUUUAAAGGAAAAAAGCAAGCUUAUAAGCUUUCAUGAAGUGUUCUUACCAGUUUUUGAUAAAUUUUUUAAAUUAUAGGAUAGAAUUGUCAUUUUAUGCAGGAGAUAUUUAUACUACGAGGGUUGUUUGGAUGGAGUCAGAUUAAAUUUUUUCAGUGAAAUUCCUAUUAUUUUAAAACUUUCCAUAUUUUCACUACGCUUGGACAUUUAACUAGGCAUUCUUUUCUUACAUCUCUAUAUGAAGAUACCUGUGUCCAAAAUUUUUGAAGAUAUAUAUUGUAUGUGUUUAUUCUUCAUAUGGUACUUUACCAUAUUUAUAUAUUGUUUUAUACCUGUAGGUUUACACACAAGUAAAUCUUUUUUUUCUUGAAUUUAAUCUGGCACUUUGCACUGCCACAGAGGUGACGAUGAACUAUGUAUAUAGUUAGAUGUUUUGAUUUCGUAAAAAAUAUAUGUCCAUCGUUUGCUAUCACCAGUACCUCUCAGCUUACUCUUCAGGGGAUAUGAAACAAUCUGUAGAUUGGUUUCCAUACAGGGAAGUUCUCUGUCCUAUGCAAUGUUUCUAAUUAAUUUGCUUAGUUCUGAGCCAUUUAUUCUGCUACACUUUGAAAGAUAUAUUAGUUCUGACUUAUUGUUUGGGGCUUUAUUUUAUUUUUAUUUUUUUGAGAUGGAGUUUCACUCUUGUUGCCCAGGCUGGAGUGCAAUAGCUCGAUCUCGGCUCACUGCAACCUCGCCUCCCUGGUUCAAGCAAUUCUCCUGCCUCAGCGAUUACAGGAAUGCACCACCACGCCCAGCUAAUUUUGUAGAGAUGGGGUUUCUCCAUGUUGGUCAGGCUGGUCUCAAACUCCUGACCUCAGGUGAUCCGCCCACCUCGGCCUUGCAAAAUGCUGGGAUUACAGGCAUGAGCCACCAUGCCCAGCCAUGUUUGGGGCUUUAUUUUAUAAGUUAGAACUUUGAAGAGGAAAUGGUGCUAUAUGUUUAUUGUUAUUACUUUGUGUAACUUUGAUGUAAUGUUUAUAAGCUAUGAGAAUCAGUUAUAAAAGUAUUAGCCAUUUGUUGUAAAUGCCAAUAAAAUAUUCACCAGGGGCAAGAAUGUACAUUUUCUUUUUAGAAAACCAAAUGUACUUUAGACAUGAAUGCAACUAUUUAAAGAAUAGCUUCAUUUAUGUUAUUCCUUACAUGUCAUAAGAUUCUUACUUAAACUUGGUCUUCUUUCAAGUUGUUUGUAUGAAGAUGCUGUACCCACUUGAACAGUCCUCAGGUGUUUACAUAAAUACUAUGUUUUACAGUUUUCAUAUUUUAAAAUAUUAAUAAAGUUAAUCGCAACGAUUCA